ACAGCUUUUCUGUCAUUCGAGGUCCUCUGCACCCGUUCUCUAAUUCUGUUCACUGAUUCAGACUUUCCAGUUAGGUGCCCCAGCUCCCCUCUCCGCUUCUCGGGUUUGAUCUUUCUCCACCCAUUCACCUGCUUCUGCAAAGGGGCUAAAGCCCAUUCUCCUUAGAGGGCAGGGGUGUAAUUAUCUGAUCAUCAGGGAGAUUGGCUCCUGGCACGUGGCAGGUGUCCCCAAACUGCCACCUUCCUCUCCCACCUUCCUUUCCCUCCCAUCUCUGCUCAGUACCCGGACGGUAACUCUAGGAAUUAUGGUUCAGGGAGGCCUUGAUCGCCCCAUCAAUCCACUUUGUCCCUGGUUUGAUUCUUGUGAGCACCAUUAACUUUUCUGGAGGAAGGUGAGGCUUUAAGAACUGUUUAAAGCCCAGGCGUGGUGGAUCACGCCUGUAAUCACAGCACUCUGGGAGGCCAAGGUGGGCAGAUCACCUGAGGUCAGGAGUUCAAGACCAGCCUAGCCAACAUGGUAAAAUCCUGUCUCUACCAAAAAUACAAAAAUUAGCUGAGCGUGGUGAUUCACACCUGUAAUCUCAGCUACUUGGGAGGCUGAGGCAGGAGAGUCGCUUGAACCUGGGAGGCGGAGGUAGCGGUGAGCCGAGAUCACGCCACUGCACUCCAGCCUAUGCAACAGAGUGAGACUCCGCCUCAAAACAACAACAACAAAAACUGUUUAAAUGAGACAGGAGGGUGUUGGGGUGUCUGUGCCCAAAAUGGGGUCUGGUGUCAUUCAACUCUUUCUUCAUUCAUUCUGCACACAGAUACUGAGCACCUGGAAAUGCACCCAGUACAGAGCCAGUUGUUAGGACACCAAAAAGAUAAGGCGUAGGACCAACCUUGGGGAUCUCUAGUCGAGAGCCGCCAAGGGUUUUUAAGGCAAGAUACCCUGGAGGGAGCUGAGGCAGUCCUAAGCCUGAAGGGCCUGGCUUAAGCUCCCUGGCAACCAUCGAGCAUCUUCCCCUUCCCACCCUGUCCCUCAGCACAGCUGCUGACAUAAACCUACUACAUGGCUGAUUGACCAUGAGAUAUGGCCAUCAAUAGACAUUGCUGAGGCGUGAAGAGCAGGUGAAGAGCAGGUGGCCAGGAAGCUAGGGGGCCAGGACUCCAGACGCAGGCCGCCCUCCACAACCCCAGCUCUCACAGUCCUCCCAGGGUCCAGACAAUGGAUCGUGCAUUUAGGUUCCCAAACACCUGCUGUGCAACGUGUAGUAGACAAAGCAGACCAAAGCCUUUGCCCUCAGGAGGCCGGCAUUCUAGCUCAGGAGCCAGCCAAGACGAUGUCGCACUGAAGAAAGACAACAAAAGUGAGAUUCACAGGAGGGAUGAGUGUGGCUGAGGCACCCGGGAAGGCCCUCGGAGAAGGUGACCUUGGGCAAAGAUCCAGACGCCAGGUGGGUGGGGCCAAAGCAGAGAAGAUCUGGAAAACCCAAUGGCUCCCCAGGGCUUCGCUCUUGCUGCAGGAGGGGAAACCACACUGCUGUGGAUUCUUCCUCCAUUCUGUCCAUUUCUCAGUUCCCAACAACACACUGAACAGUAGGAGGCCAGUUCUCCGCUCACAGCGGGCGCUGCACCCCAGGUGCUGCUCUCGAGAAAAAGGCGAGCAUGGACCAAUUUAGUGGCUCCGAGGUAUGAAAAGCAGUGAGAUGGUGUCUUUGAGGGAGUUAGUGAUAGGCUGAGACCCCCUUGCUGUCCCCCCUGAAGCCUGGUGACCAGAGCUGCCAGGAGGCCACACAGAGAGAGGUUUAUGAUGGGGGACCUGGAAUUCGGAAGGGGCAGAGUGGUCAGGUGACCCAUACACGCCUGAGAAAACUGAUGUGGAGAGCUGUGUUGUCAUUCUGAGGCAGGAAAUAGAGACAGACUGACAGACAGACAGAAAGACACGGGCACAUUGAGAGACAGAGACAGAAUCACAGAGCAGAGCUGGCUUCUCACCAGCAGGCGUGGGCACACCUGAGAGAGCAUCCAGAGAGGUUAGAAAUCUUCCUUAGGUCCUCCUGGGAGGCUCAGGUGACCCCAGUGGGAAACAUGAAAGGCUGGGAGGACUUCCAGGGCUGAGAGAAGGAAGCUACGCAGCCGGCCGGUGCCACAUUCCCUGUGCCUUGGGGAGUGUCCCCCAGUGUCCCCAGCCAUGCACCCUGGGGGGAGUCGGCUUGGACAUCUGUGCCACCCCUUGACAGGCAGAGUGGGGGCCACAACCUGGGCCCUCCAGUGCUGGUCAGCAGAGGCUGCCCCCGCCCCUUGCCUUCCUCCUCCCGCUCCUUCCUCCAGCCCUGGGAAGGUCGGAAGCCACCACCAUGGGGCUAGUGCGGAAGCAGAGGGAGAACAGAGGGGCCCUCCUCGCAAAAACUAAAACAAGCCCACAGCCUGUGCAGAACCGCACCCGGGUGUGAUCACUCCUUACCCCACACACCCACUGCCACUUGGAGAUGGCUUCAUGGCUGCAGUCACAGGGCACCCUGUGUUGUCAGGGGUGAGCCAGUGAGGCCCGGGACCUGCCCAGGGGUGCAUCAAGGGUGGAGAAGACCUGGCCCCAGCGCAGGUGUGAACAGGCAGGAGGGCUGGGGAGGGAAUAGCGCUGGGUUGUGGCCGAGCCCCCAAGCCCUGCUCUUGAGAGGCACUGGCUACACACUCGGCCCCUACCCAGACAGGACCCCAAUUCCUCCCUGGCCCCUCUGUGUUCCUGCAUCUUCCCAGCCCCUCACCUCCUCUGGCGUGGCCUCACCUCCAGCCGGGAUGCCCCAUUAGCUGCUCACCCAAGCUGCUAGAACCUCAGGCUAAUGGCCCUGUCACCCGCCCUCCUCCCCUUCCGGCUCACUGCCCAUCCCGGGCAUCCUCCAUCAGCCCGCUGAGGGGACUGCUGAGCCUCAGAGACAUCUGGCAGCACCAGGAGAGUCUCAGAAAUCGAGAAGCUUUCUUCCUCUGGGACCUGUGCGCCACAUCCUAUCUCCUGUGACGCUGCAGGAGCUUCCCUGGUUUUAAGAGGUGACAUGGUGGAGAGAAAGCACAGGACUGGGGGCCACAGGUCCUGGCUUCUCAUCCAGGCUCCGCUGCUCCCUGACUGCUGCCUUUCUCUGUGGGCCUCGUUUCCUCCCUGAUCCCACCAGGUGAAUUGUAAUUCUCCACACAGGGCUGGAACCCGCGAGUGAUCCCAGGAGCCCCUCCUCUCCGGGGCCCCAAGAUCUGAGGACAGGGAGCCAGGUUGCACACAGGAGCCGUGCAGGCCAGGACGGCGGCCCCAUGGACCUGCCCCCGCAGCUCUCCUUCGGCCUCUAUGUGGCCGCCUUUGCGCUGGGCUUCCCGCUCAACGUCCUGGCCAUCCGAGGCGCGACGGCCCACGCCCGGCUCCGUCUCACCCCUAGCCUGGUCUACGCCCUGAACCUGGGCUGCUCCGACCUGCUGCUGACAGUCUCUCUGCCCCUGAAGGCGGUGGAGGCGCUAGCCUCCGGGGCCUGGCCUCUGCCGGCCUCGCUGUGCCCCGUCUUCGCGGUGGCCCACUUCUUCCCACUCUAUGCCGGCGGGGGCUUCCUGGCCGCCCUGAGUGCAGGCCGCUACCUGGGAGCAGCCUUCCCCUUGGGCUACCAAGCCUUCCGGAGGCCGUGCUAUUCCUGGGGGGUGUGCGCGGCCAUCUGGGCCCUCGUCCUGUGUCACCUGGGUCUGGUCUUUGGGUUGGAGGCUCCAGGAGGCUGGCUGGACCACAGCAACACCUCCCUGGGCAUCAACACACCGGUCAACGGCUCUCCGGUCUGCCUGGAGGCCUGGGACCCGGCCUCUGCCGGCCCGGCCCGCUUCAGCCUCUCUCUCCUGCUCUUUUUUCUGCCCUUGGCCAUCACAGCCUUCUGCUACGUGGGCUGCCUCCGGGCACUGGCCCGCUCCGGCCUGACGCACAGGCGGAAGCUGCGGGCCGCCUGGGUGGCCGGCGGGGCCCUCCUCACGCUGCUGCUCUGCGUAGGACCCUACAACGCCUCCAACGUGGCCAGCUUCCUGUACCCCAAUCUAGGAGGCUCCUGGCGGAAGCUGGGGCUCAUCACGGGUGCCUGGAGUGUGGUGCUUAAUCCGCUGGUGACCGGUUACUUGGGAAGGGGUCCUGGCCUGAAGACAGUGUGUGCGGCAAGAACGCAAGGGGGCAAGUCCCAGAAGUAACGCCACUGCUCGGGGGAAGGAGCAUGGGGCAGGAGGGCCCGGCUGCUUCUCCAGGCCCCUGCGGGGGGCUGCUUCGGAGGAACUGCAGGGCAGCCUGGCCCGGAGGCCUCCCUGGAGCCACUCAAGCAGAGAGCGGCGCCUGCUGAGGGCAGCACCCCAGUCAAGAGAGGAGCACCGAGCCAGAGCACGGUGGCAGGGGGAGGUAAGUUUGCCCCUGCACGUGUCGAGGAAGUUUGUCCCUUCCUCGCCUAUCUUUCUCUCCCCUCUGCACGUCCUCACCUGCCUGUCUUCCGUGGGCCGCGAGCAGAGGCCUUGUACUUACGGGAAGGAGGAGGCAGUCUGUUUCUGACCCACAGGAACUGCCACUCCGGUGAUGCACUUGAGGACAGCUACUCUGAAAUCAGUUCCCAGGAGAGAACAUUUGAUUUCCGAGUAGGAGAGGAGGCAGGAGGCAGGAUAAUGACGCUGUUAUACCAUGUGAAACUCGCAAGGGGGCAGCCUUGGAGCUUGGAACGGAGGCUGGCAGGAAAAGAUGCUUCAGCCGGGGAGGGAAAAUGCAAGGUCCCGCAGUGAUGGGCAAAGGCUACGGAGUUGACUCUUGAACAACGUGGGGAUGGGGUGCCGAACCCCACGCAGUGGAAAAUCUGUGCAUGACUUUGACUCCCCCAAAGUUCAACUACUAAUAGCCUACUGUUGACCAAAAGCUUUACCCAGUAUAUAAACAAUUGAGUAAGACAUAUUUGAAGCCAGGCACAGUGGCUUAUGCCUGUAAUCCCAGCACUUUAGGAGGCCGAGGCGGGAAGACUGCUCGAAGCCAGGAGUUCAAGAGCAGCCUGGGCAAGAUAGUGAGACCCCCACCUCUACAAAUAAUAAAAAUAAAAAUAAUUAGCUGGGCGUGGUGGUGCGUGCCUGUAGUCCCAGCUACUCAGGGGUCUGAGGUGGGAGGAUCCCUUGAGCCCAGGAUUGAGGCUGCAAUGCCAUGAUCGCACCACUGCACUCCAGCCUGGGUGACAGAGCAAGAUCCUGUCUCUGGAAAAAAAAGAAAAAAGACAUAUUUUGUAUGUUAUAUAUAUUAUGUGCUGUAUUCUUACAAUAAAGUAAGCUAGAGAAAAGUACAUGUUACUGAAAACAUUAUUAGAAAGAGAAAAUACCUUCACAGCACUGUGCUGUAUUUAUCAAUACUGUAAGUUUUGUUGUCUGUUUAUAAGAGAAGUUGUCUGUCUCAAGCGGCAGUAACCGCGGCUGCAGAUCUCAAUCUGUGGUAGAUAUCAAGCAGUUCAACCCUUUUUUAUAAUGUCAUGACUUUUCUUUGCUUCUUGGAAGCAGCUCUGGCAUCACUAGUGGCCCCGCAUUUGGGGCCAAGGGGGUUAUUCAAAGUUUACGGUAUUGCAUUAAACAUGGUGAAACAUA